GCUCUAAGCUGCAGCAAGAGAAACUGUGUGUGAGGGGAAGAGGCCUGUUUCGCUGUCGGGUCUCUAGUUCUUGCACGCUCUUUAAGAGUCUGCACUGGAGGAACUCCUGCCAUUACCAGCUCCCUUCUUGCAGAAGGGAGGGGGAAACAUACAUUUAUUCAUGCCAGUCUGUUGCAUGCAGGCUUUUUGGCUUCCUACCUUGCAACAAAAUAAUUGCACCAACUCCUUAGUGCCGAUUCCGCCCACAGAGAGUCCUGGAGCCACAGUCUUUUUUGCUUUGCAUUGUAGGAGAGGGACUAAGUGCUAGAGACUAUGUCGCUUUCCUGAGCUACCGAGAGCGCUCGUGAACUGGAAUCAACUGCUUCAGGGAAAAAGAAAAAAAAAAAAAAAAGACUUGCCUGGGAGGCCGCGAGAAACUUGCAUUGGAAGCUUCAGCAACCAGCAUUCGAGAAACUCCUCUCUACUUUAGCACGGUCUCCAGACUCAGCCGAGAGACAGCAAACUGCAGCGCGGUGAGAGAGCGAGAGAGAGGGAGAGAGAGACUCUCCAGCCUGGGAACUAUAACUCCUCUGCGAGAGGCGGAGAACUCCUUCCCCAAAUCUUUUGGGGACUUUUCUCUCUUUACCCACCUCCGCCCCUGCGAGGAGUUGAGGGGCCAGUUCGGCCGCCGCGCGCGUCUUCCCGUUCGGCGUGUGCUUGGCCCGGGGAACCGGGAGGGCCCGGCGAUCGCGCGGCGGCCGCCGCGAGGGUGUGAGCGCGCGUGGGCGCCCGCCGAGCCGAGGCCAUGGUGCAGCAAACCAACAAUGCCGAGAACACGGAAGCGCUGCUGGCCGGCGAGAGCUCGGACUCGGGCGCCGGCCUCGAGCUGGGAAUCGCCUCCUCCCCCACGCCCGGCUCCACCGCCUCCACGGGCGGCAAGGCCGACGACCCGAGCUGGUGCAAGACCCCGAGUGGGCACAUCAAGCGACCCAUGAACGCCUUCAUGGUGUGGUCGCAGAUCGAGCGGCGCAAGAUCAUGGAGCAGUCGCCCGACAUGCACAACGCCGAGAUCUCCAAGCGGCUGGGCAAACGCUGGAAGCUGCUCAAAGACAGCGACAAGAUCCCUUUCAUUCGAGAGGCGGAGCGGCUGCGCCUCAAGCACAUGGCUGACUACCCCGACUACAAGUACCGGCCCAGGAAGAAGGUGAAGUCCGGCAACGCCAACUCCAGCUCCUCGGCCGCCGCCUCCUCCAAGCCGGGGGAGAAGGGAGACAAGGUCGGUGGCAGUGGCGGGGGCGGCCAUGGGGGCGGCGGCGGCGGCGGGAGCAGCAACGCGGGGGGAGGAGGCGGCGGUGCGAGUGGCGGCGGCGCCAACUCCAAACCGGCGCAGAAAAAGAGCUGCGGCUCCAAAGUGGCGGGCGGCGCGGGCGGUGGGGUUAGCAAACCGCACGCCAAGCUCAUCCUGGCAGGCGGCGGCGGCGGCGGGAAAGCAGCGGCUGCCGCCGCCGCCUCCUUCGCCGCCGAACAGGCGGGGGCCGCCGCCCUGCUGCCCCUGGGCGCCGCCGCCGACCACCACUCGCUGUACAAGGCGCGGACUCCCAGCGCCUCGGCCUCCGCCUCCUCGGCAGCCUCGGCCUCCGCAGCGCUCGCGGCCCCGGGCAAGCACCUGGCGGAGAAGAAGGUGAAGCGCGUCUACCUGUUCGGCGGCCUGGGCACGUCGUCGUCGCCCGUGGGCGGCGUGGGCGCGGGAGCCGACCCCAGCGACCCCCUGGGCCUGUACGAGGAGGAGGGCGCGGGCUGCUCGCCCGACGCGCCCAGCCUGAGCGGCCGCAGCAGCGCCGCCUCGUCCCCCGCCGCCGGCCGCUCGCCCGCCGACCACCGCGGCUACGCCAGCCUGCGCGCCGCCUCGCCCGCCCCGUCCAGCGCGCCCUCGCACGCGUCCUCCUCGGCCUCGUCCCACUCCUCCUCUUCCUCCUCCUCGGGCUCCUCGUCCUCCGACGACGAGUUCGAAGACGACCUGCUCGACCUGAACCCCAGCUCAAACUUUGAGAGCAUGUCCCUGGGCAGCUUCAGUUCGUCGUCGGCGCUCGACCGGGACCUGGAUUUUAACUUCGAGCCCGGCUCCGGCUCGCACUUCGAGUUCCCGGACUACUGCACGCCCGAGGUGAGCGAGAUGAUCUCGGGAGACUGGCUCGAGUCCAGCAUCUCCAACCUGGUUUUCACCUACUGAAGGGCGCGCAGGCAGGGAGAAGGGCCGGGGGGGGUAGGAGAGGAGAAAAAAAAAGUGAAAAAAAGAAACGAAAAGGACAGACGAAGAGUUUAAAGAGAAAAGGGAAAAAAGAAAGAAAAAGUAAGCAGGGCUGGCUUCGCCCGCGUUCUCGUCGUCGGAUCAAGGAGCGCGGCGGCGUUUUGGACCCGCGCUCCCAUCCCCCACCUUCCCGGGCCGGGGACCCACUCUGCCCAGCCGGAGGGACGCGGAGGAGGAAGAGGGUAGACAGGGGCGACCUGUGAUUGUUGUUAUUGAUGUUGUUGUUGAUGGCAAAAAAAAAAAAGCGACUUCGAGUUUGCUCCCCUUUGCUUGAAGAGACCCCCUCCCCCUUCCAACGAGCUUCCGGACUUGUCUGCACCCCCAGCAAGAAGGCGAGUUAGUUUUCUAGAGACUUGAAGGAGUCUCCCCCUUCCUGCAUCACCACCUUGGUUUUGUUUUAUUUUGCUUCUUGGUCAAGAAAGGAGGGGAGAACCCAGCGCACCCCUCCCCCCCUUUUUUUAAACGCGUGAUGAAGACAGAAGGCUCCGGGGUGACGAAUUUGGCCGAUGGCAGAUGUUUUGGGGGAACGCCGGGACUGAGAGACUCCACGCAGGCGAAUUCCCGUUUGGGGCUUUUUUUUCCUCCCUCUUUUCCCCUUGCCCCCUCUGCAGCCGGAGGAGGAGAUGUUGAGGGGAGGAGGCCAGCCAGUGUGACCGGCGCUAGGAAAUGACCCGAGAACCCCGUUGGAAGCGCAGCAGCGGGAGCUAGGGGCGGGGGCGGAGGAGGACACGAACUGGAAGGGGGUUCACGGUCAAACUGAAAUGGAUUUGCACGUUGGGGAGCUGGCGGCGGCGGCUGCUGGGCCUCCGCCUUCUUUUCUACGUGAAAUCAGUGAGGUGAGACUUCCCAGACCCCGGAGGCGUGGAGGAGAGGAGACUGUUUGAUGUGGUACAGGGGCAGUCAGUGGAGGGCGAGUGGUUUCGGAAAAAAAAAAAGAAAAAAAGAAAAAAAAAGAAAAAAAAAAGAUUUUUUUCUUCUCUUAAUCGGAAUCGUGAUGGUGUUGGAUUAUUUCAAUGGUGGGGUUAAUAUAGCAUGUUAUCCUGUCUAUCUUUUAAAGAUUUCUGUAUAAGACUGUUGAGCAGUUUUUAAAAUAGUGUAGGAUAAUAUAAAAAGCAGAUAGAUGGCGCUAUGUUUGAUUCCUACAACGAAAUUAUCACCAGCUUUUUUUCAUUCUUAACUCUUUAAAGGAUUCAAACGCAACUCAAAUCUGUGCUGGACUUUAAAAAAACAAUUCAGGACCAAAUUUUUUCUCAGUGUGUGUGUUUAUUCCUUAUAGGUGUAAAUGAGAAGACGUGUUUUUUUCCUUCACCGAUGCUCCAUCCUCGUAUUUCUUUUUCCUUGUAAAUGUAAUCAGAUGCCAUUUUAUAUGUGGACGUAUUUAUACUGGCCAAACAUAUUUUUUCUUUUGUCCCUUUUUUUCUUUCCUUUCUUUUUACUUCCUUUAUUUCUUUAUUCCUUCCUUUUCCUUUUUUUCUUUUUUUUUUCUUUUUUUUUUUUUUUUUUUGGUAGUUGUUGUUACCCACGCCAUUUUACGUCUCCUUCACUGAAGGGCUAGAGUUUUAACUUUUAAUUUUUUAUAUUUAAAUGUAGACUUUUGACACUUUUAAAAAACAAAAAAAGACAAGAGAGAUGAAAACGUUUGAUUAUUUUCUCAGUGUAUUUUUGUAAAAAAUAUAUAAAGGGGGUGUUAAUCGGUGUAAAUCGCUGUUUGGAUUUCCUGAUUUUAUAACAGGGCGGCUGGUUAAUAUCUCACACAGUUUAAAAAAUCAGCCCCUAAUUUCUCCAUGUUUACACUUCAAUCUGCAGGCUUCUUAAAGUGACAGUAUCCCUUAACCUGCCACCAGUGUCCACCCUCCGGCCCCCGUCUUGUAAAAAGGGGAGGAGAAUUAGCCAAACACUGUAAGCUUUUAAGAAAAACAAAGUUUUAAACGAAAUACUGCUCUGUCCAGAGGCUUUAAAACUGGUGCAAUUACAGCAAAAAGGGAUUCUGUAGCUUUAACUUGUAAACCACAUCUUUUUUGCACUUUUUUUAUAAGCAAAAACGUGCCGUUUAAACCACUGGAUCUAUCUAAAUGCCGAUUUGAGUUCGCGACACUAUGUACUGCGUUUUUCAUUCUUGUAUUUGACUAUUUAAUCCUUUCUACUUGUCGCUAAAUAUAAUUGUUUUAGUCUUAUGGCAUGAUGAUAGCAUAUGUGUUCAGGUUUAUAGCUGUUGUGUUUAAAAAUUGAAAAAAGUGGAAAACAUCUUUGUACAUUUAAGUCUGUAUUAUAAUAAGCAAAAAGAUUGUGUGUAUGUAUGUUUAAUAUAACAUGACAGGCACUAGGACGUCUGCCUUUUUAAGGCAGUUCCGUUAAGGGUUUUUGUUUUUAAACUUUUUUUUGCCAUCCAUCCUGUGCAAUAUGCCGUGUAGAAUAUUUGUCUUAAAAUUCAAGGCCACAAAAACAAUGUUUGGGGGAAAAAAAAGAAAAAAUCAUGCCAGCUAAUCAUGUCAAGUUCACUGCCUGUCAGAUUGUUGAUAUAUACCUUCUGUAAAUAACUUUUUUUGAGAAGGAAAUAAAAUCAGCUGGAACUGAACCCUAAA